GCUGGGAGAGCUCCUGUUUUCCGCCCCAACUUCGUUCUCUUCUUGAAGGCCGCUCUCCUUAAGCACGUAACCCGGCUACUUUCCGGUACUGCGAUCUCAUUGGCUGCAUGUUCUGUCAGUUCCAGAAGCUGGCCAAUGAGAUGCCGCUGCUGGCGGCCUUCUCGACCCCGUGGACCCAGAGGUUCCCCCGUGGGAUCGGAGCAGUUAGAAGGGGAGGAGAGGGAAGGUGUGGCAGGCGCCGAGCAAAUGGAACUUGUUUGCUUCAUUCUUAUGUACCUACCUUUGCACCUUGUAAUCAUCCUUUAUGCCUCAGAUUGUUAUUUUGUGUCAGUAAGUAAUCCAUAAAGUGCCAACAUGGGAAAGAAACGGACAAAGGGAAAAACUGUUCCAAUCGAUGAUUCCUCUGAAACUUUAGAACCUGUGUGCAGACACAUUAGAAAAGGAUUGGAACAAGGUAAUUUGAAAAAGGCUUUAGUGAAUGUGGAAUGGAAUAUCUGCCAAGACUGUAAGACUGACAAUAAAGUGAAAGAUAAAGCUGAAGAAGAAACAGAAGAAAAGCCUUCAGUUUGGCUGUGUCUUAAAUGUGGCCAUCAGGGCUGUGGCAGAAAUUCUCAGGAGCAGCAUGCCUUGAAGCACUAUCUGACGCCAAGAUCUGAACCUCACUGUCUGGUUCUUAGUUUGGACAACUGGAGUGUAUGGUGUUACGUAUGUGAUAAUGAGGUCCAGUAUUGUAGUUCAAACCAGUUGGGUCAAGUGGUUGAUUAUGUCAGAAAACAAGCCAGCAUUACAACUCCAAAGCCAGCAGAGAAAGAUAAUGGAAAUAUUGAACUUGAAAAUAAAAAAUUAGAAAAAGAGAGUAAGAAUGAACAAGAGAGAGAAAAGAAGGAAAACAUGGCUAAAGAGAAUCCUCCCAUGAAUUCUCCUUGCCAAAUAACCGUGAAAGGACUCAGUAAUUUGGGAAACACAUGUUUCUUCAAUGCAGUUAUGCAGAACUUGUCACAAACACCAGUGCUUAGAGAACUACUAAAAGAAGUGAAAAUGUCUGGAACAAUUGUAAAAAUUGAACCACCUGAUUUGGCAUUAACAGAACCAUUAGAAAUAAACCUUGAGCCUCCAGGCCCUCUUACUUUAGCCAUGAGCCAGUUUCUUAAUGAGAUGCAAGAGACCAAAAAGGGGGUUGUGACACCGAAAGAACUCUUUUCUCAGGUCUGUAAAAAAGCAGUGCGGUUUAAAGGCUAUCAGCAGCAAGACAGCCAGGAGCUGCUUCGCUACUUAUUGGAUGGGAUGAGAGCAGAAGAACACCAAAGAGUGAGUAAAGGAAUACUUAAAGCAUUUGGUAAUUCUACUGAAAAGUUGGAUGAAGAACUAAAAAAUAAAGUUAAAGAUUAUGAGAAGAAAAAAUCAAUGCCAAGUUUUGUUGACCGCAUCUUUGGUGGUGAACUAACUAGUAUGAUCAUGUGUGAUCAAUGCAGAACUGUCUCCUUGGUUCAUGAAUCUUUCCUUGAUUUGUCCCUCCCAGUUUUAGAUGAUCAGAGUGGUAAGAAAAGUGUAAAUGAUAAAAAUCUGAAAAAGACAGUGGAGGAUGAAGAUCAAGAUAGUGAGGAAGAAAAAGAUAACGACAGUUACAUAAAAGAGAGAAGUGAUAUUCCUUCUGGAACAAGUAAGCACUUACAGAAAAAAGCAAAGAAACAAGCCAAAAAGCAAGCCAAGAACCAACGAAGACAACAAAAAAUUCAAGGAAAAGUUCUUCAUUUAAAUGAUAUUUGUACUAUUGACCAUCCUGAAGACAGUGAAUAUGAAGCUGAAAUGUCACUUCAAGGAGAAGUAAAUAUUAAAUCCAACCAUAUUUCACAAGAGGGUGUUAUGCAUAAAGAAUAUUGUGUCAACCAGAAAGAUUUGAAUGGCCAAGCAAAAAUGAUCGAAAGUGUAACUGACAAUCAAAAAUCCACAGAGGAAGUAGAUAUGAAAAAUAUCAACAUGGAUAAUGAUCUGGAGGUUUUAACAUCUUCUCCCACUAGGAAUUUAAAUGGUGCCUACCUAACGGAAGGGAGCAAUGGAGAAGUGGACAUUUCCAAUGGUUUCAAAAACCUAAAUUUGAAUGCUGCUCUUCAUCCUGAUGAAAUAAAUAUAGAGAUUCUGAAUGAUAGUCAUACUCCUGGAACAAAGGUGUAUGAGGUUGUAAAUGAAGAUCCAGAAACUGCUUUCUGUACUCUUGCAAACAGGGAAGUUUUCAAUACUGAUGAGUGUUCAAUCCAACAUUGUUUAUAUCAGUUCACCCGUAAUGAGAAACUUCGAGAUGCGAAUAAACUGCUUUGUGAAGUAUGCACACGGAGACAGUGUAAUGGACCAAAGGCAAAUAUAAAAGGUGAAAGGAAGCAUGUUUACACCAAUGCCAAAAAGCAGAUGCUAAUUUCUCUUGCUCCUCCUGUUCUUACUCUUCAUUUAAAGAGAUUUCAGCAGGCUGGUUUUAACCUACGCAAAGUUAACAAACACAUAAAGUUUCCGGAAAUCUUAGAUUUGGCUCCUUUUUGCACCCUUAAAUGUAAGAAUGUUGCAGAAGAAAAUACAAGGGUACUCUAUUCCUUAUAUGGAGUUGUUGAACACAGUGGUACUAUGAGGUCGGGGCAUUACACUGCCUAUGCCAAGGCAAGAACCGCAAAUAGUCAUCUCUCUAAUCUUGUUCUUCACGGUGAUAUUCCACAAGAUUUUGAAAUGGAAUCAAAAGGGCAGUGGUUUCACAUCAGCGACACACAUGUGCAAGCUGUGCCUACAACUAAAGUACUAAACUCACAAGCGUACCUCCUAUUUUAUGAGAGAAUACUGUAAUAAUAUCAAAAGCACUUUUUCUGGAAACACAUUUAUGGCUUUUAUAAUGGCUGAAAUAACGAUAAAAAAAGACUAAUUAAAAUCAUGUUCACUUAACAUUAAAUACAUGCCAGAAGAAAUCAUGUUUAUUUAAAUAUUGAAGGGAAAAAUACCUAAAAAUGUACAAAGGUUUUAUAUUGUCAUAGUGGUUUUUAUUCCUGCUUUGUUUCUGGAAAGGAAAUCCUGAAUUACUUAAGUACUUUGUGUUUAAUAUAUCUGGGUGAUGGAUCACAACACAUCAAUAAACUGACUUACCCUAAAA